GCGUCCGGGAGGAGCCAACCGUGGCGCAGGCGGCGCGGGGAGGCGUCCCAGAGUCUCACUCUGCCGCCCAGGCUGGACUGCAGUGACACAAUCUCGGCUGACUGCAACCACUGCCUCCAGGGUUCAAGCGAUUCUCUUGCCUCAGCCUCCCAAGUAGCUGGGAUUACAGAUUGAUGUUCAUGUUCCUGACACUACUACAAGAUUCAUACUCCUGAUGCUACUGACAACGUGGCUUCUCCACAGUCACCAAACCAGGGAUGCUAUACUGGACUUCCCUACUCUCAUCUGCUCCAGCCCCCUGACCUUAUAGUUGCCCAGCUUUCCUGGCAAUUGACUUUGCCCAUCAAUACACAGGAUUUAGCAUCCAGGGAAGAUGUCGGAGCCUCAGAUGUUAAUUUUCUAAUUGAGAAUGUUGGCGCUGUCCGAACCUGGAGACAGAGUAUCAGCGCCUUUGCUUGCUGCUGUUUUUGCUGUUUUUUGAUGCUGGGAACCACCACCUAAAGAUAGUAAAGAAAACACAGGAAGCUUUCCGGUAACUCAUGCUAAAGAAACACAAAAUCACCCCAGUGCCUUGAGAAAUUUCCUUUCCCUCUCUAACUUUCCCCUUCAGUGUUCUAAAGGGAAGGCGUUUCUGGUAAGGUGUAGUUGCGUAAAUGAUGGCUGCCUACUUCAGCAAGCAAGAACUGUUGGAGUAUUAAGCAUGGGUAACUGGAUAUUCUGGUUUGGGCACUGGAGGAUCCCUGGAAGCCGGAAGCAGGCUGUUGCUGCCGGGGUAGGGGCGGCGGGGGUGGGAGGUAGAAACUUAUUGCUGUGAUUUUAUAGGCAGUAAACUGAUGCUUAGAGAGGUUCAGCACUCGCCCAAGCUCACACACCUACUAAACUGUGGAGCUAGGAUUUGAAUCCAGCUACAAAUUUAGUUGUCAUUGAAAUGUCUAAAUGCACUCUACUGCGCAAGCGAUAGGAACUUCCCAGCGGAGCUCAGCUCAGGGACGCUUGCAGCUCCCCGCGCCCCGCUCGACUCUCCGGCCGCGGCUCCGCGGGCUCCUCCCCCUCGGUCCCUGCCCCUUUUGCGCCCUCUGCUGGUCUCUAGGGAAAGCGCAUCUCCUGAAAUCAGAAGUCGCACCCAAGCUGUCCCGUUUCCUUAGCUCCUAGUAAAGCGAUAUGACCCAUCCAUCCCCUCCUCCUCAAAGCCUCACAUGAAUCUUCUUUGAGGUACUCUCUGAUGCUUCACUCUUCAGCGCUGAGAAAAAUGGGGAGGAAGGGGAAGUGAAUGUAUUAGUAUAGCCCCUUCUCAAAACCAAUCGUGCAGCAUCUUAGCCAUGCCUUAUCCUGGAAGAACGAGGCAGCUCACGUGGGCAUGGGGGUAAUGAGCAGGGAGGCAAUUACAGACUCUUAGGUUCUCACCGCUAACAGUGUGGUCAGUGGACCAGCAGCAGCAUCACGUGGGAGCCCGUUAGAAAUGCAGACUCUCAGGUCCUUCAGCCACAGCCCUGAUGAAUCAGAAUCACCGUUUCAAGGAGGUCUCAGGCGGGCCGUUUCAGGUUCCGAGCUCGCUUUGAGGCUCUGUGGAUGUUUUGCAGCAUAUUCAAUUUUGUUUUGUUCAAAGGUCACAGUGACAACUAAGUUUGCAGCGGGAUUCAAAUCCGAGCUCCACAGUGUAAUAAAUGUGAGAUCUUAGACAAGUGCUUAACCUCUCUGAGUUAAUCAUCUAUCAAAUAAUGAAAAGCACUAUAAGCCAACUCUUCAACUUUCAGGACAUUGUUCACCCGAAACCCGAAAUCCAAUAACUGUGCACUGUCUUCUAACACAGCCAUAAUUUACCUAGAUGUACCGCUUAGAAAUGUCUCACUCUCAUAGUGACCUUAGUUCUAUCUGUCCCUAGAGAGCCGCAAGACCAUUUUGUCUGGAAGUUCUCUGCUCACUGGACAAUAGGGACAGUGGAAUUGUCCUCAUCCUUGUGCUUGAGUCUUUGGAAACCAAAUGACCCCAGAAAUGUCAUGAAAGAGAUUUUUAGGUCCCAGAGGAACUGAAUGGCUUAGACACCCACCUUCUGAACAAGAGGCUGGGCCAGAGAUUUCUCAAGGUCCCAACUUCAACCUUGGUGUUCUGUCCGCCUUGAUUUACAAAAUGGUCUUGAUCUUUUCCAAUUAAAAUUCCAUUUAGUAGAGAUACACAGAAAGUUUGCAAUUCUUCCACAAGAAAACUGCUGUAUGGCAUAGAAAAAUAUCUACAUAAUAUUUUUUGUUUCUUCUUCUUAAUUAGCUUUCCUAUUUUCCCUUAGGAAAACAAAAAGUCCUUUCUCCUGAUUCACCAAAAAAUAAAAUACUGACUACCAUCACUGUGAUGAGAUUCCUAUAGUCUCAGGAACUGAAGUCUUUAAACAACCAGGGACCCUCUGCCCCUAGAAUAAGAACAUACUAGAAGUCCCUUCUGCUAGGACAACGAGGAUCAUGGGAGACCACCUGGACCUUCUCCUAGGAGUGGUGCUCAUGGCCGGUCCUGUGUUUGGAAUUCCUUCCUGCUCCUUUGAUGGCCGAAUAGCCUUUUAUCGUUUCUGCAACCUCACCCAGGUCCCCCAGGUCCUCAACACCACUGAGAGGCUCCUGCUGAGCUUCAACUAUAUCAGGACAGUCACUGCUUCAUCCUUCCCCUUUCUGGAACAGCUGCAGCUGCUGGAGCUCGGGAGCCAGUAUACCCCCUUGACUAUUGACAAGGAGGCCUUCAGAAACCUGCCCAACCUUAGAAUCUUGGACCUGGGAAGUAGUAAGAUAUACUUCUUGCAUCCAGAUGCUUUUCAGGGACUGUUCCAUCUGUUUGAACUUAGACUGUAUUUCUGUGGUCUCUCUGAUGCUGUAUUGAAAGAUGGUUAUUUCAGAAAUUUAAAGGCUUUAACUCGCUUGGAUCUAUCCAAAAAUCAGAUUCGUAGCCUUUACCUUCAUCCUUCAUUUGGGAAGUUGAAUUCCUUAAAGUCCAUAGAUUUUUCCUCCAACCAAAUAUUCCUUGUAUGUGAACAUGAGCUCGAGCCCCUACAAGGGAAAACGCUCUCCUUUUUUAGCCUCGCAGCUAAUAGCUUGUAUAGCAGAGUCUCAGUGGACUGGGGAAAAUGUAUGAACCCAUUCAGAAACAUGGUGCUGGAGAUACUAGAUGUUUCUGGAAAUGGCUGGACAGUGGACAUCACAGGAAACUUUAGCAAUGCCAUCAGCAAAAGCCAGGCCUUCUCUUUGAUUCUUGCCCACCACAUCAUGGGUGCCGGGUUUGGCUUCCAUAACAUCAAAGAUCCUGACCAGAACACAUUUGCUGGCCUGGCCAGAAGUUCAGUGAGACACCUGGAUCUUUCACAUGGGUUUGUCUUCUCCCUGAACUCACGAGUCUUUGAGACACUCAAGGAUUUGAAGGUUCUGAACCUUGCCUACAACAAGAUAAAUAAGAUUGCAGAUGAAGCAUUUUACGGACUUGACAACCUCCAAGUUCUCAAUUUGUCAUAUAACCUUCUGGGGGAACUUUACAGUUCGAAUUUCUAUGGACUACCUAAGGUAGCCUACAUUGAUUUGCAAAAGAAUCACAUUGCAAUAAUUCAAGACCAAACAUUCAAAUUCCUGGAAAAAUUACAGACCUUGGAUCUCCGAGACAAUGCUCUUACAACCAUUCAUUUUAUUCCAAGCAUACCCGAUAUCUUCUUGAGUGGCAAUAAACUAGUGACUUUGCCAAAGAUCAACCUUACAGCGAACCUCAUCCACUUAUCAGAAAACAGGCUAGAAAAUCUAGAUAUUCUCUACUUUCUCCUACGGGUACCUCAUCUCCAGAUUCUCAUUUUAAAUCAAAAUCGCUUCUCCUCCUGUAGUGGAGAUCAAACCCCUUCAGAGAAUCCCAGCUUAGAACAGCUUUUCCUUGGAGAAAAUAUGUUGCAACUUGCCUGGGAAACUGAGCUCUGUUGGGAUGUUUUUGAGGGACUUUCUCAUCUUCAAGUUCUGUAUUUGAAUCAUAACUAUCUUAAUUCCCUUCCACCAGGAGUAUUUAGCCAUCUGACUGCAUUAAGGGGACUAAGCCUCAACUCCAACAGGCUGACAGUUCUUUCUCACAAUGAUUUACCUGCUAAUUUAGAGAUCCUGGACAUAUCCAGGAACCAGCUCCUAGCUCCUAAUCCUGAUGUAUUUGUAUCACUUAGUGUCUUGGAUAUAACUCAUAACAAGUUCAUUUGUGAAUGUGAACUUAGCACUUUUAUCAAUUGGCUUAAUCACACCAAUGUCACUAUAGCUGGGCCUCCUGCAGACAUAUAUUGUGUGUACCCUGACUCGUUCUCUGGGGUUUCCCUCUUCUCUCUUUCCACGGAAGGUUGUGAUGAAGAGGAAGUCUUAAAGUCCCUAAAGUUCUCCCUUUUCAUUGUAUGCACUGUCACUCUGACUCUGUUCCUCAUGACCAUCCUCACAGUCACAAAGUUCCGGGGCUUCUGUUUUAUCUGUUAUAAGACAGCCCAGAGACUGGUGUUCAAGGACCAUCCCCAGGGCACAGAACCUGAUAUGUACAAAUAUGAUGCCUAUUUGUGCUUCAGCAGCAAAGACUUCACAUGGGUGCAGAAUGCUUUGCUCAAACACCUGGACACUCAAUACAGUGACCAAAACAGAUUCAACCUGUGCUUUGAAGAAAGAGACUUUGUCCCAGGAGAAAACCGCAUUGCCAAUAUCCAGGAUGCCAUCUGGAACAGUAGAAAGAUCGUUUGUCUUGUGAGCAGACACUUCCUUAGAGAUGGCUGGUGCCUUGAAGCCUUCAGUUAUGCCCAGGGCAGGUGCUUAUCUGACCUUAACAGUGCUCUCAUCAUGGUGGUGGUUGGGUCCUUGUCCCAGUACCAGUUGAUGAAACAUCAAUCCAUCAGAGGCUUUGUACAGAAACAGCAGUAUUUGAGGUGGCCUGAGGAUCUCCAGGAUGUUGGCUGGUUUCUUCAUAAACUCUCUCAACAGAUACUAAAGAAAGAAAAAGAAAAGAAGAAAGACAAUAACAUUCCGUUGCAAACUGUAGCAACCAUCUCCUAAUCAAAGGAGCAAUUUCCAACUUAUCUCAAGCCACAAAUAACUCUUCACUUUGUAUUUGCACCAAGUUAUCAUUUUGGGGUCCUCUCUGGAGGUUUUUUUUUUCUUUUUGCUACUAUGAAAACAACAUAAAUCUCUCAAUUUUCGUAUCAACACCAUGUUCUGUCUCACUAACCUCCAAAUGGAAAAUAAUAGAUCUAGAAAAUUGCAACUGCCCUUAGAGGUUUCCAGUCUCCAUUGAUUUUCUUUCAGAUCCAAUAAUACCGUUCUGUCCUGCUGUGUUGAUUAUGGAAUGUAUCCUAAUCAUGGGAAGGGCACCUUGGGAGAAGUUGCAGAUGGCUGACGUGCUUUCUCUAGCAUUCAGCUAAAAAAUGGGAUGGUCCAUGAUUCUGCGUUCUCUGUGUUCUGCAAAACAACAUUAAGUAGAAAACAAACAGAAGCAGAGGCACAUUUCCUUCUUUUGCCACAGAAACAAUGCCACUGUUGAGUGCAAGUCACACUUUGUCUCAUAGAUAAGAGGUGGCCCCAAAGAAGCUGGGAUGAAUGAGUCACUACCUGUCUUGUGACUGUACUGCACUUCAUGUUCUUACCUUCGGCUUCUCCAGGUCUCGCCCUAGUGAGCCAAGAACUUUCUCUCACAUGCUGCCUUUAUUUAAGCCUGGCCUUCAAGACCUUCCAUGAUUUAUCACCAACCUACCUUUUCAGCUUUGUUUCCUAGCACACCUCAUUGAUCAGCUGCUCAGGCUGUUGCAUGAAGAACAUGGACUUUGCACACAGAUCCUGGGUUGAGUUCUGAGUCAGCUGUGUAUUAGCCAUGUAACCUUGGCCUUGGUAUGCCCUUGCUGGACCUACAUUUUCUCACGUAACAGCAUCUAUGUCAUAGAAUUCCUGUGAAAAUUAAAUUGGCCAAGGAUGUCAGGGCUUCUCAGAUCUUUUCCUUCGUUGCCCUAAUGACCACAAGAGAACACAUACACUGAAGGCCUCCUGGGGGGCAGUUGCAAUUUCACUGAAGUUGUAUUUUUUUAUCUUAAAUGAAAUCUAUGUGUAUUUUCCA